GAGAGAGACGUCGGACAAGCCUGGGAAUGAUCACCCUUCUCCCGAAACGCAGAGACUCUAACGGGAACUCCUGACCCCGCUUACUCACCUACAACCAGAUAUUCCCCCUGCUUUCUGCGCCCAGGUUUCUCCUCCGGCUGUGGAGGGCGGGGGUCCCCUAGGCCCUUGGGACUUGGGCGUGGCUUACCAUCGCAGCCGUGGUGUGAACUGUAUCGUGCCCAGGCUCCAAUGCGCCCUGUGCUUUGAACUGGGGGCUUCCUAGGGCUUGAGGCUGCUUGAGGCUGUGCUCGUACCCCAGGGAACCGGCAGCGUUGGAACUCCGCGGCGCUGUUGCGGCUCUUGCCCCAUCCUCCAUCCCUGUGCCAAUCAGGGACUUCCUUCUAGGCCGCCUGCAUACAGUGCGAACAUAAGUAUACCCCCCUUCGCACAUUUAUUGAGCUCCUGUUGCGUGCAGAGCUUAUACAUCACACAUCUGUGACGGGCCCCUCAGUCAGGCGACGGCUCCGAGCCGCGAACACAGCCAAGAGCACCGGACCUCAGCCGAUCCUCCAAGUCCCAGCCCCUAUGACUCUCCCAACUCGGUUCCGUGACUAGAACCUGCAGCCCGGAGACUCGGAACUUUGGGCAGCCACGUGGGCGCGGGAUUCCGACAUGGGUCGCUCGUCCACAGCAACUCAACCCUAGAAGUCGCAUUUAGGGAGCCCAUGACUCUGAAGUUGACCCUGGCCUGACUAACCCUCUAACCCUCGCUCGAUCCAGGCUGAAACAUCUAGAUUUGCGGAGCGCGGGAAAGUGCCUGGAUUCCAGCGCAUCUGUAUGGCACCCGGGUCUGCGUCCACGCGGGCCUCCACGGCGCGCUUGGCCUGGCUCAGCCCCUGCAUCUACAAAAGACGCCGGUCCUUUGGAUCGCGAUGCAGUCAACAGCAGCUCCCCUAGCAGGACUCCUCCGUCUUGCUCAUGACUGGGUCCCCUGGGCAGAGCCAGGUCCUGGCAGAGAGCAGAUAUCCAGUAAAUACCUCUUGGCCCUAAGAAUGACUGGGAACACUCAUGUAGCGAGAACACCUUCCUGUGUGUUAUCUCAUCUCAUCCUCACAGCAGCCCAGAGAGCAGAAGAUGGCUGUGCCACCCACGUAUGCCGAUCUUGGCAAAUCUGCCAGGGAUGUCUUCACCAAGGGCUAUGGAUUUGGCUUAAUAAAGCUUGAUUUGAAAACAAAAUCUGAGAAUGGAUUGGAAUUUACAAGCUCAGGCUCAGCCAACACUGAGACCACCAAAGUGACGGGCAGUCUGGAAACCAAGUACAGAUGGACUGAGUACGGCCUGACGUUUACAGAGAAAUGGAAUACCGACAAUACACUAGGCACCGAGAUUACUGUGGAAGAUCAGCUUGCACGUGGACUGAAGCUGACCUUCGAUUCAUCCUUCUCACCUAACACUGGGAAAAAAAAUGCUAAAAUCAAGACAGGGUACAAGCGGGAGCACAUUAACCUGGGCUGCGACAUGGAUUUCGACAUUGCUGGGCCUUCCAUCCGGGGUGCUCUGGUGCUAGGUUACGAGGGCUGGCUGGCCGGCUACCAGAUGAAUUUUGAGACUGCAAAAUCCCGAGUGACCCAGAGCAACUUUGCAGUUGGCUACAAGACUGAUGAAUUCCAGCUUCACACUAAUGUGAAUGACGGGACAGAGUUUGGCGGCUCCAUUUACCAGAAAGUGAACAAGAAGUUGGAGACCGCUGUCAAUCUUGCCUGGACAGCAGGAAACAGUAACACGCGCUUCGGAAUAGCAGCCAAGUAUCAGAUUGACCCUGACGCCUGCUUCUCGGCUAAAGUGAACAACUCCAGCCUGAUAGGUUUAGGAUACACUCAGACUCUAAAGCCAGGUAUUAAACUGACACUGUCAGCUCUUCUGGAUGGCAAGAACGUCAAUGCUGGUGGCCACAAGCUUGGUCUAGGACUGGAAUUUCAAGCAUAAAUGAAUACUGUACAAUUGUUUAAUUUUAAACUAUUUUGCAGCAUAGCUACCUUCAGAAUUUAGUGUAUCUUUUAAUGUUGUAUGUCUGGGAUGCAAGUAUUGCUAAAUAUGUUAGCCCUCCAGGUUAAAGUUGAUUCAGCUUUAAGAUGUUACCCUUCCAGAGGUACAGAAGAAACCUAUUUCCAAAAAAGGUCCUUUCAGUGGUAGACUCGGGGAGAACUUGGUGGCCCCUUUGAGAUGCCAGGUUUCUUUUUUAUCUAGAAAUGGCUGCAAGUGGAAGCGGAUAAUAUGUAGGCACUUUGUAAAUUCAUAUUGAGUAAAUGAAUGAAAUUGUGAUUUCCUGAGAAUCGAACCUUGGUUCCCUAACCCUAAUUGAUGAGAGGCUCGCUGCUUGAUGGUGUGUACAAACUCACCUGAAUGGGACUUUUUUAGACAGAUCUUCAUGACCUGUUCCCACCCCAGUUCAUCAUCAUCUCUUUUACACCAAAAGGUCUGCAGGGUGUGGUAACUGUUUCUUUUGUGCCAUUUUGGGGUGGAGAAGGUGGAUGUGAUGAAGCCAAUAAUUCAGGACUUAUUCCUUCUUGUGUUGUGUUUUUUUUUGGCCCUUGCACCAGAGUAUGAAAUAGCUUCCAGGAGCUCCAGCUAUAAGCUUGGAAGUGUCUGUGUGAUUGUAAUCACAUGGUGACAACACUCAGAAUCUAAAUUGGACUUCUGUUGUAUUCUCACCACUCAAUUUGUUUUUUAGCAGUUUAAUGGGUACAUUUUAGAGUCUUCCAUUUUGUUGGAAUUAGAUCCUCCCCUUCAAAUGCUGUAAUUAACAACACUUAAAAAACUUGAAUAAAAUAUUGAAACCUCAUCCUUCUUCUGUUGUCUUUAUUAAUAAAAUAUAAAUAAACAGGG